GGUGGGUGGCGGCAUGGCCUGGACGUGAGGACAUUUCUGGGCGGGAUUGGCGGCCGGAGGCUAGGCCUGGCGUGCCGCAACCAACCGGUCCAGGCGGCAGGACUGGGCUCUUGUUUGAAACUUUGAGCGACUCUCGCGUGUGCGUGCCCCUUUCAUCCGCGCGUGCCAGCCAUUCCCCUGGGCUCCUUACUUUUCAACCAUUGCAGGAACCUACUCCUACCGAAGGGAUCGGGACGCAGGCUUUGGGAUCCAUCCCCAGUUCCCGCCCGGGGAGCGAGGCCGAGACGCCUUUGGGAGACCUGCUGGGUCAGGUCUCCCUGAGCCGCAGCCGGAAGCGAAAGGGGUCGAGGGGCCCAUAUAGGUCACCUGUCCUUGCGGCCCGCGUCUUCGGCCUGCUUGGGAGCUGCUGGAGCGGAGGCGUAGGGCGGUGUCGGCCCUAGAGUUCUCACAGCUGGUGAACGGGGAUGUGGCUUUGCUGGGCGGGGGCCCCUACAUGCUCUGCACUGAUGGGCAGCAGCUAUUGCGACAGGUCCUGCACCCCGAGGCCUCCAGGAAGAACCUGGUGCUCCCCGACAUGUUCUUCUCCUUCUAUGACCUCCGAAGAGAAUUCCAUAUGCAGCAUCCAAGCACCUGCCCUGCCAGGGACCUCACUGUGGCCACCAUGGCACAGGGUUUAGGACUGGAGACAGAUGCCACAGAGGAUGACUUUGGGGUCUGGGAAGUCAAGACAAUGGUAGCUGUUAUCCUCCAUCUACUCAAAGAGCCCAGCAGUCAAUUGUUUUCGAAGCCCGAGGUGAUAAAGCAGAAAUACGAGACGGGGCCUUGCAGCAAGGCUGAUGUGGUGGACAGUGAGACUGUGGUACGGGCUCGUGGGUUGCCGUGGCAGUCAUCAGACCAGGACGUGGCUCGCUUCUUCAAAGGGCUCAACGUGGCCAGGGGUGGUGUAGCACUCUGCCUCAACGCCCAGGGCCGCAGAAAUGGCGAGGCCCUCAUCCGCUUUGUGGACAGCGAGCAGCGGGACCUAGCGCUGCAGAGACACAAGCACCACAUGGGCGUCCGCUAUAUUGAGGUGUAUAAAGCGACAGGGGAGGAGUUUGUAAAGAUUGCAGGGGGCACAUCACUAGAGGUGGCUCGUUUCUUGUCACGGGAAGACCAAGUGAUCCUGCGGCUGCGGGGACUGCCCUUCUCGGCUGGGCCAACGGACGUGCUUGGCUUCCUGGGGCCAGAGUGCCCAGUGACUGGGGGUACCGAGGGGCUGCUCUUUGUGCGCCAUCCUGAUGGCCGGCCGACUGGUGAUGCCUUCGCCCUCUUUGCUUGUGAGGAGCUGGCACAGGCUGCACUGCGCAGGCACAAGGGCAUGCUGGGUAAGCGAUACAUUGAACUCUUCCGGAGCACUGCAGCCGAAGUGCAGCAGGUCUUGAACCGCUAUGCAUCCGGCCCACUCCUUCCUACACUGACUGCCCCACUGCUGCCCAUCCCCUUCCCACUGGCACCUGGGACUGGGAGGGACUGUGUACGCCUCCGAGGCCUGCCCUACACGGCCACCAUUGAAGACAUCCUGAGCUUUCUGGGGGAGGCAGCAGCUGACAUUCGGCCCCACGGUGUACACAUGGUGCUCAACCAGCAGGGCCGGCCAUCGGGCGAUGCCUUCAUUCAGAUGACAUCAGCAGAGCGAGCCCUAGCUGCUGCUCAGCGUUGCCAUAAGAAGGUGAUGAAGGAGCGCUACGUGGAGGUGGUCCCCUGUUCCACAGAGGAGAUGAGCCGAGUGCUGAUGGGGGGCACCUUGGGCCGCAGUGGCAUGUCCCCUCCACCCUGCAAGCUGCCCUGCCUCUCACCACCUACCUACACCACCUUCCAAGCCACCCCAACGCUCAUUCCCACGGAGACGGCAGCUCUAUACCCCUCUUCAGCACUGCUCCCAGCUGCCAGGGUGCCUGCUGCCCCCACCCCUGUUGCCUACUAUCCAGGGCCAGCCACUCAACUCUACCUGAACUACACAGCCUACUACCCAAGCCCCCCAGUCUCCCCCACCACUGUGGGCUACCUCACUACACCCACUGCUGCCCUGGCCUCUGCUCCCACCUCAGUGUUGUCCCAGUCAGGAGCCUUGGUCCGCAUGCAGGGUGUCCCAUACACGGCUGGUAUGAAGGAUCUGCUCAGCGUCUUCCAGGCCUACCAGCUACCCGCUGAUGACUACACCAGUCUGAUGCCUGUUGGUGACCCACCUCGCACUGUGUUACAAGCCCCCAAGGAAUGGGUGUGUUUGUAGGAGAGAAAGCCAGGAGGUAAGAGCCAGCUGAUAUCCUCGGCGAACAUGUCUCUCCUGAGUCCAGAAGACCAGCACCCUCAACCUGGUAGCUUCUUUCUGGCUUGUCAAAGCUCUCAGAAGGUACCUAGAGGAGCCCAAGCCCCAGCUCCAUCCUCCACUUAUUCUGCCUGUUUCCCCCAAAGACAAUGGCUGGACCCUGCAUGCAGGGCUGGGGGUGGAAUGGGGCUAACCAGCUCCUGAUGGCCUGAGCCAGGCAUCUUGACUGGCACCUGGAGAGCCCUUAAGUCUGUCCUGGCUGUGGCCCAUGCCGACAGAUAUCGUGGGGCUGACAGGUCCACGGCAGGCUUGCUUUCUUUUAUAAAAUGGAAGCUCUGGUACCUUCAAUGUAUGACUCCUGGGAGAAUCAAGGGUCCAUCUGAGCCUCUGAGUAAAGAUCCCAAUGUUCUACCUCUCCCUGUCCCUCUUGUAGGGGAUAGGGAGGCAGAGAGAGCCAGCCCCUACCCUCAGAGUAUCUGGACCUCAGAGACCAUGUUGUGCCAGGGGUGGUCCCACCUAAAGAUGCUAGCCCCUCUCCAGGUGGGCAUAAGGAGUAACAGAUGGCAAAACCACAAACUAUUUUGAUGGACUGUGCUGCAGUAUCACCAGAAGACAUUAGGGGGCAGUAGGCCCCCACACAAAACCUUCAGGCUUGAAUUUUAAAGGGGAGGACUUUCUGCCAACUUUUCUUGUAUGCCUUGGGAAAGCCAGUUGCCCUGAACCCAGCAGACACCAUGGAAUGUCCUUUGCACGCAUUAAAUGGUACAGAACUGAAGCCUCGGAAGCAAUUUGGAACUCGAUCUUCUCUUCCUUAAAUGAAAAGUUAUUGACCAAAUGGACUUUUUAAAAGACACAGGACCCUUAACUUUGCCCCAAAGUGAGGGGCUCCACACCAACCCCAGGCGGAGGAACACUCAGACAGAUUAAGGAUACUGUUGACCUGUCACUGUUUAUUAUUUCAGCACUAAAACUGAGGAGCCUCAACUGCUGGCUCUUCUUCCCUUUGUAUUUGUGUAAGGAGCACUGCACUCCCAUAAAAGGUUUUAAAAUACAAAAUGUACAAGAACACACAAUUCCAAGUGCUGUAAACAUAACUGAGAACCAGUUCCUUUACUAAACAUCCAUUUUAUAAAACACAAGGUUUCAAUUUGAGCCCA